CCAUGGGAUUGUUUGAGAAUUACCAACAUGUAGGGAAAACCUGCGAUCCUGGCCUGCAGAGGGAGGGGAGGACCCCUUUUGCCAGGCUCCCCCAAACAUUGAGCUCUCAGCUUCACCAGCUGCACCCCAUGGGGUCUUCUUUGCCAGCUUUGGCGAGGGUCUGUUCCUCACUGCGCCAAUGCCCCGGCAUGUGAUCUUUGGGCUCAGUGCCAGGCCCAGCUAUCCUGCUGGCACAGUAGGAAGCCAGAAAAGCCCCUACCCACUCCUGCUAGAGCCUAGGGGCUGCUGUUCCCUCUAGGACUCCACCAGGGAGCAGGAGGGGCCUUCACGGGGCUGGUGCAGACCUAAGACCUCCCACGCUUGCCCUCAGCCAGAGCCCUGAGACCCACACCCUCCUCUGCCACCUCCAGAAAAAGCCUCCGGUCCUGGGCACCUUUGAUGACUUCCUUUCCCAUCCGUGCUGCUGGAGAUGUCUACACUAGGAACUCACUGGGAUGGAGCUGUGUCCUGCAGGAAGGGCGGGGUGAGAGCCGGCCAGUGUCUGAGCUCCAGGAAUGGCAAAGAGGAAGCUGCACAAUAUUUCCCAGCCUCGCCGCUCCUGCUAUUUGCCAACCGCCGGGACGUACGGCUGGUGGACGCCGGCGGAGUCAAGCUGGAGUCCACCAUCGUGGUCAGCGGCCUGGAGGAUGCGGCCGCAGUGGACUUCCAGUUUUCCAAGGGAGCCGUGUACUGGACAGACGUGAGCGAGGAGGCCAUCAAGCAGACCUACCUGAACCAGACGGGGGCCGCCGUGCAGAACGUGGUCAUCUCCGGCCUGGUCUCUCCCGACGGCCUCGCCUGCGACUGGGUGGGCAAGAAGCUGUACUGGACGGACUCAGAGACCAACCGCAUCGAGGUGGCCAACCUCAAUGGCACAUCCCGGAAGGUGCUCUUCUGGCAGGACCUUGACCAGCCGAGGGCCAUCGCCUUGGACCCCGCUCACGGGUACAUGUACUGGACAGACUGGGGUGAGACGCCCCGGAUUGAGCGGGCAGGGAUGGAUGGCAGCACCCGGAAGAUCAUUGUGGACUCGGACAUUUACUGGCCCAAUGGACUGACCAUCGACCUGGAGGAGCAGAAGCUCUACUGGGCUGACGCCAAGCUCAGCUUCAUCCACCGUGCCAACCUGGACGGCUCGUUCCGGCAGAAGGUGGUGGAGGGCAGCCUGACGCACCCCUUCGCCCUGACGCUCUCCGGGGACACUCUGUACUGGACAGACUGGCAGACCCGCUCCAUCCAUGCCUGCAACAAGCGCACUGGGGGGAAGAGGAAGGAGAUCCUGAGUGCCCUCUACUCACCCAUGGACAUCCAGGUGCUGAGCCAGGAGCGGCAGCCUUUCUUCCACACUCGCUGUGAGGAGGACAAUGGCGGCUGCUCCCACCUGUGCCUGCUGUCCCCAAGCGAGCCUUUCUACACAUGCGCCUGCCCCACGGGUGUGCAGCUGCAGGACAACGGCAGGACGUGUAAGGCAGGAGCCGAGGAGGUGCUGCUGCUGGCCCGGCGGACGGACCUACGGAGGAUCUCGCUGGACACGCCGGACUUCACCGACAUCGUGCUGCAGGUGGACGACAUCCGGCACGCCAUUGCCAUCGACUACGACCCGCUAGAGGGCUAUGUCUACUGGACAGAUGACGAGGUGCGGGCCAUCCGCAGGGCGUACCUGGACGGGUCUGGGGCGCAGACGCUGGUCAACACCGAGAUCAACGACCCCGAUGGCAUCGCGGUCGACUGGGUGGCCCGAAACCUCUACUGGACCGACACGGGCACGGACCGCAUCGAGGUGACGCGCCUCAACGGCACCUCCCGCAAGAUCCUGGUGUCGGAGGACCUGGACGAGCCCCGAGCCAUCGCACUGCACCCCGUGAUGGGCCUCAUGUACUGGACAGACUGGGGAGAGAACCCUAAAAUCGAGUGUGCCAACUUGGAUGGGCAGGAGCGGCGUGUGCUGGUCAAUGCCUCCCUCGGGUGGCCCAACGGCCUGGCCCUGGACCUGCAGGAGGGGAAGCUCUACUGGGGAGACGCCAAGACAGACAAGAUCGAGGUGAUCAAUGUUGAUGGGACGAAGAGGCGGACCCUCCUGGAGGACAAGCUCCCGCACAUUUUUGGGUUCACGCUGCUGGGGGACUUCAUCUACUGGACUGACUGGCAGCGCCGCAGCAUCGAGCGGGUGCACAAGGUCAAGGCCAGCCGGGACGUCAUCAUUGACCAGCUGCCCGACCUGAUGGGGCUCAAAGCUGUGAAUGUGGCCAAGGUCGUCGGAACCAACCCGUGUGCGGACAGGAACGGGGGGUGCAGCCACCUGUGCUUCUUCACACCCCACGCAACCCGGUGUGGCUGCCCCAUCGGCCUGGAGCUGCUGAGUGACAUGAAGACCUGCAUCGUGCCUGAGGCCUUCUUGGUCUUCACCAGCAGAGCCGCCAUCCACAGGAUCUCCCUCGAGACCAAUAACAACGACGUGGCCAUCCCGCUCACGGGCGUCAAGGAGGCCUCAGCCCUGGACUUUGAUGUGUCCAACAACCACAUCUACUGGACAGACGUCAGCCUGAAGACCAUCAGCCGCGCCUUCAUGAACGGGAGCUCGGUGGAGCACGUGGUGGAGUUUGGCCUUGACUACCCCGAGGGCAUGGCCGUUGACUGGAUGGGCAAGAACCUCUACUGGGCCGACACUGGGACCAACAGAAUCGAAGUGGCGCGGCUGGACGGGCAGUUCCGGCAAGUCCUCGUGUGGAGGGACUUGGACAACCCGAGGUCGCUGGCCCUGGAUCCCACCAAGGGCUACAUCUACUGGACCGAGUGGGGCGGCAAGCCGAGGAUCGUGCGGGCCUUCAUGGACGGGACCAACUGCAUGACGCUGGUGGACAAGGUGGGCCGGGCCAACGACCUCACCAUUGACUACGCUGACCAGCGCCUCUACUGGACCGACCUGGACACCAACAUGAUCGAGUCGUCCAACAUGCUGGGUCAGGAGCGGGUCGUGAUUGCCGACGAUCUCCCGCACCCGUUCGGUCUGACGCAGUACAGCGAUUAUAUCUACUGGACAGACUGGAAUCUGCACAGCAUUGAGCGGGCCGACAAGACUAGCGGCCGGAACCGCACCCUCAUCCAGGGCCACCUGGACUUCGUGAUGGACAUCCUGGUGUUCCACUCCUCCCGCCAGGAUGGCCUCAAUGACUGUAUGCACAACAACGGGCAGUGUGGGCAGCUGUGCCUUGCCAUCCCCGGCGGCCACCGCUGCGGCUGCGCCUCACACUACACCCUGGACCCCAGCAGCCGCAACUGCAGCCCGCCCACCACCUUCUUGCUGUUCAGCCAGAAAUCUGCCAUCAGUCGGAUGAUCCCGGACGACCAGCACAGCCCGGAUCUCAUCCUGCCCCUGCAUGGACUGAGGAACGUCAAAGCCAUCGACUAUGACCCACUGGACAAGUUCAUCUACUGGGUGGAUGGGCGCCAGAACAUCAAGCGAGCCAAGGACGACGGGACCCAGCCCUUUGUUUUGACCUCUCUGAGCCAAGGCCAAAACCCAGACAGGCAGCCCCACGACCUCAGCAUCGACAUCUACAGCCGGACACUGUUCUGGACGUGCGAGGCCACCAAUACCAUCAACGUCCACAGGCUGAGCGGGGAAGCCAUGGGGGUGGUGCUGCGUGGGGACCGCGACAAGCCCAGGGCCAUCGUCGUCAACGCGGAGCGAGGGUACCUGUACUUCACCAACAUGCAGGACCGGGCAGCCAAGAUCGAACGCGCAGCCCUGGACGGCACCGAGCGCGAGGUCCUCUUCACCACCGGCCUCAUCCGCCCUGUGGCCCUGGUGGUGGACAACACACUGGGCAAGCUGUUCUGGGUGGACGCGGACCUGAAGCGCAUUGAGAGCUGUGACCUGUCAGGGGCCAACCGCCUGACCCUGGAGGACGCCAACAUCGUGCAGCCUCUGGGCCUGACCAUCCUUGGCAAGCAUCUCUACUGGAUCGACCGCCAGCAGCAGAUGAUCGAGCGUGUGGAGAAGACCACCGGGGACAAGCGGACUCGCAUCCAGGGCCGUGUCGCCCACCUCACUGGCAUCCAUGCAGUGGAGGAAGUCAGCCUGGAGGAGUUCUCAGCCCACCCAUGUGCCCGUGACAAUGGUGGCUGCUCCCACAUCUGUAUUGCCAAGGGUGAUGGGACACCACGGUGCUCAUGCCCAGUCCACCUCGUGCUCCUGCAGAACCUGCUGACCUGUGGAGAGCCGCCCACCUGCUCCCCGGACCAGUUUGCAUGUGCCACAGGGGAGAUCGACUGUAUCCCCGGGGCCUGGCGCUGUGACGGCUUUCCCGAGUGCGAUGACCAGAGCGACGAGGAGGGCUGCCCCGUGUGCUCCGCCGCCCAGUUCCCCUGCGCGCGGGGUCAGUGUGUGGACCUGCGCCUGCGCUGCGACGGCGAGGCAGACUGUCAGGACCGCUCAGACGAGGCGGACUGUGACGCCAUCUGCCUGCCCAACCAGUUCCGGUGUGCGAGCGGCCAGUGUGUCCUCAUCAAACAGCAGUGCGACUCCUUCCCCGACUGUAUCGACGGCUCCGACGAGCUCAUGUGUGAAAUCACCAAGCCGCCCUCAGACGACAGCCCGGCCCACAGCAGUGCCAUCGGGCCCGUCAUUGGCAUCAUCCUCUCUCUCUUCGUCAUGGGUGGUGUCUAUUUUGUGUGCCAGCGCGUGGUGUGCCAGCGCUAUGCGGGGGCCAACGGGCCCUUCCCGCACGAGUAUGUCAGCGGGACCCCGCACGUGCCCCUCAAUUUCAUAGCCCCGGGCGGUUCCCAGCAUGGCCCCUUCACAGGCAUCGCAUGCGGAAAGUCCAUGAUGAGCUCCGUGAGCCUGAUGGGGGGCCGGGGCGGGGUGCCCCUCUACGACCGGAACCACGUCACAGGGGCCUCGUCCAGCAGCUCGUCCAGCACGAAGGCCACGCUGUACCCGCCGGGGCUCGGAUCUGGCUGUAUGCUUUCCAGGAUGGCCUUGGAGACCCACAUAAGCCCUACACCCUUUGGGAAGCUGCAUGUUGGGUUGGGGUGCCGUCAGUGGCACUUGUGGAAGGUGCAGACCUGUGUGGAUCCUGAACCCGCCGCCCUCCCCGGCCACGGACCCCUCCCUGUACAACAUGGACAUGUUCUACUCUUCAAACAUUCCGGCCACUGCGAGACCGUACAGGCCCUACAUCAUUCGAGGAAUGGCGCCCCCGACGACGCCCUGCAGCACCGACGUGUGUGACAGCGACUACAGCGCCAGCCGCUGGAAGGCCAGCAAGUACUACCUGGAUUUGAACUCGGACUCAGACCCCUAUCCACCCCCACCCACGCCCCACAGCCAGUACCUGUCGGCGGAGGACAGCUGCCCGCCCUCGCCCGCCACCGAGAGGAGCUACUUCCAUCUCUUCCCGCCCCCUCCGUCCCCCUGCACGGACUCAUCCUGACCUCGGCCGGGCCACUCUGGCUUCUCUGUGCCCCUGUAAAUAGUUUUAAAUAUGAACAAAGAAAAAAAUAUAUUUUAUGAUUUAAAAAAUAAAUAUAAUUGGGAUUUUAAAAACAUGAGAAAUGUGAACUGUGAUGGGGUGGGCAGGGCUGGGAGAACUUUGUACAGUGGAGAAAUAUUUAUAAACUUAAUUUUGUAAAACAGAA